GUUUAGCGACCGGACCCGAAACGGGGAAGUUGUCUUGUUUGGAGAGGUUAGUAGAGCAGCGCGCGCGUCACCAGAGUCGUUUCUCUUCGGAGUCUUAGGUGAUCGAGGGUGUGCCCAGGGGGCGGACUUGUUUGCGCCUCCCGUUCCCUCCCAAUUUCCAAACGUGUCACCCCGGCGCCGACGGCCCUGUGCAGGGGAAGCAGAUGGAGUUCAAGCUGGAGGCUCAUCGCAUCGUCAGCAUCUCUCUGGGCAAGAUCUACAACUCGCGGGUCCAGCGCGGCGGCAUCAAGCUGCAUAAGAACCUCCUGGUCUCGCUGGUGCUGCGCAGCGCCCGCCAAGUCUACCUGAGCGACCCGUGCCCCGGCCUCUACCUGGCCGGUCCCGCUGGGACCCCGGCGCCGCCACCGCAGCAGCAGCCCGGGGAGCCGGCGGCCGGGCCACCCGCCGGCUGGGGAGAGCCGCCCCCGCCCGCCGCUCGUGCCUCUUGGCCGGAGACCGAGCCGCAGCCGGAGCGCUCCUCCGUCUCAGACGCGCCGCGGGUAGGGGACGAGGUGCCGGUGGCCACGGUGACUGGAGUCGGGGACGUUUUUCAGGGCGGAGAGGCGGACGCGACGGAAGCUGCCUGGAGCCGCGUGGAGGGGCCGCGCCAGGCGGCGGCCAGAGAAGCCGAGGGUACCGCCGGAGGCUGGGGCGUCUUCCCCGAGGUAUCUCGUGCCGCGCGCCGCCCCUGCGGCUGCCCCCUAGGCGGGGAGGACCCGCCGGGUACACCGGCCGCGACCCCCCGCGCUGCCUGCUGCUGCGCGCCGCAACCAGCGGAGGACGAGCCCCCCGCGCCGCCCGCGGUGUGCCCCAGGAAGCGCUGCGCGGCGGGGGUGGGCGGCGGCCCAGCGGGCUGCCCGGCGCCCGGCUCGACCCCGCUCAAGAAGCCCCGCCGGAACUUAGAGCAGCCGCCGAGUGGAGGAGAGGACGACGACGCGGAGGAGAUGGAGACCGGGAACGUGGCUAACCUCAUCAGCAUCUUCGGUUCCAGUUUCUCGGGACUCCUACGGAAAAGCCCCGGGGGCGGCAGAGAGGAAGAGGAGGGAGAGGAGAGCGGUCCGGAAGCCGCCGAGCCCGGGCAGAUCUGCUGCGAUAAGCCGGUGCUGAGAGACAUGAACCCCUGGAGCACAGCCAUCGUGGCCUUCUGAGCCCUUGGCCCCCCUGCGGGGAGGAGGUGGAGCAGCGGGCGUCCCCGAAGUGAGGGCCAGGCCCUUCCCGGCUGCGAGGACGCCCAGAGACCGCGGGCGCUGAGCGCGUUGGGCAGACUGGUUGCCUCUGGGCAUCGCAAACUGCCCCCGGGCGCAUCUGGCUUAUCUGGAGACCUGGGAGCUUGAGGCUCAUUGGAAGAGGACGAUCGUUAACUUUUGUGUUUGUGUAUGUCUGUGUAUGUAAGUUUGUCUUGUGGCAUUAAGACUAUUUUGCUCUUCUGGAAUGCACCACUCCUUCCCCAGGGUUUAAGAGAUUGGGGGCAGACAGGGACUUUCCUCUGCCGGCUGCGUGGAGAAGGAAGCGGCUAAAAGGUUUGGGCCGGGGAGUUCCCCAUUCGUUCUCCGGGGAGGGAGGGACUUUACACCUACCCCUCACCGGAAAGCUAGACCCGCUUCAGGGCCAGGAGUGGCGUUUCCGCACAGGAUUUCCUAAGACGAGAGGGAUUUAGCCAAGAGCACAGACUUGGAUUCCUUCUGUCCCUCCCCACCUUUCUCUCCCAAUGAAGAAACGUUUAUAUCCUGUGAUUACUCUAGGAAAGGGGCGUAUUAACGGUCCUUUGCUUCCCCGCAGGGGAGAAAAAGCUUGACGAACUUCACAGAAGAGUUCAAGCUUGGAAAUAAUGGAGUUUAUAGAGAAAAGAUAUAUUUUUAAAAGCUCUAGGUCAGAAGUACUACACAGUGCUUUUAAAAAGUGUUUAAUGAGAGUUUACAGACAGAAGCCCGAAGUGGAAAGACCUUAUGGUUUUGUAGAUAUGGUGACUCCAGUCUUUGUUGUAUAAAGGUUGGGGGAGCUGAUAAGGUUUUUGUACAGUAUUUUCUCCUUCGUUGUAUUGAUUUUUGUAUAAAAAUGUAACUUCUACGUGUCUAACACGUAUUAAAUAUUUUGAAGCAACGUAACUGCCUGCUUGUCUGUAAUAACCUGCCUGGGUUGGGAGGGAAGUGGGAGGAGGGAAACCAGGGCCUGAGCUAGAAAAUUGAAGGUGUGGUUCUUAGUAUCAGUCAUUCGCAGACUGAGGACAUUGUUUACUGACUCCACUAAGUAUCAAGAGAGACACGUUUAAUUUUUCCUCCUAGAUCAGAGGACUGCUAUUAGAUACUAAUAUCGGCGACCUGUCAGGUUCUAGAAACCUGCCACUACAACUGCCUUUUCUAAGGUCAGUUUAGACCAAUUUGUCACCCAAUAUGUGGGUGUCUAAUACUAAGUAAUUUAACCAACUUUUGAAGCCCCGCUUAUCCACAAAAAUGUUUUUCAGCAAAACUUUGUUUCCUGUUAAGCUAUUAAUACGGGUCAUCUUUUAGCUUUGUAAUUGAAAAAAAAAAAGUUUAGAUAGUAGUUUACCUUAAAAGCCCAUUCGAACUGACAUAGGAAGAUGAAAGAGACUGACUUGUCCAAAUUGUCAGGUCCACCUCUGCAUCACAGUGGAUGUCAGGAUGUAAAUUUUCAGUUUUUCUCUUACAUCUAGAAAGUAAAUAUAUUGCUGAGAGGGAAAUUGUUUGCAUCAAACCAGAUAAGGAAGGAGGGCUAGGCAAAUUUAGUUCUCAUUUAGCAAAACUUCCUGAUUUGUUUUGUUACUUAAAUGGUGACAUCAGUGUUUGGUCAUGGUAGACACUUAGGUGAUGAUAGCCAAAACAUCCAUCGAUUUUACUAAAAUCACUGCCAUUAAGAGAGUUUUUUGUCUCUUCAUGUUCAAUGUUUGAAAGGUAUUCAGUAAUCUAUUUCAGAAGCAAAUCAAUUAGGGAAUGGUGUUUAUUAAAAUACGGUACAGUUGCCAGGACUUUAAAAGAUGGUACUGGUUUCUAACAACUUACGAGUAUAUAGGGUAUUUAAAAGAUGGGAGAGAUUGAAGAAAGACAAAGGUUUAAAGGUCAUAGCCUUCGAGCAUAAGAGGCAUAUGAAUGGUGUCUUGGCCUUAACUCCCAAUUAUACGAACUUCUGUUUUAGCUGAAUAGGCCAGUGCCUCGUGCCUUGAUAUUUCGGCAAAUCUAUUAGUGGUUCCUUAAGCAUAGGGAACUUUGUACUUUAUGCUCUGUCGCCAUAAUAAUGUAUUUAUAGAAUUAAACAUUCUCAAAUUAGGGUCUUGUUAAACUGACUUUUUCUUUCAGAAAGUAGCUACUUAAAUUCUGUUACAGCUACAAAAGAUCCAUCAAGUGCUGACUGCUUAAACUGAAGAAGGUGUCCAGGGCCUUAAUUCUGCAAACAUUUCCUGUUGUUAGAAAGUAUGAUGCUUGAACAGCGAUCUCAGUGUAUUUUAUGUUUUAAAGGGGGUAACGUUUGGUGUGUUUAAGAGAGCUGAUGUGUUUUGGAUGAGACUAAAGUUGAUCCUUGGUUUUACAUUAAGAUGAACCUGGGUCCAUGUGUCUGCUUAAAGAAUGUAAAUUGGCAUACUUGAUAGGAGGAUAAAGCUUUGUAGGAAUUAGAAAAGAUCAUUCUCUUUUUUGUUGCAGAAGCAGUAUAGUAUAGUAGUUAGAGCAUGGGCCCUGGAGCCAGGCUGCUUGGUGUCUUCCUUUAUUUAUUUAUUUAUUUAAUUAUAAAAAGUAAAUAUAAAGUGAGCUAUGUUGACCAGGUUCGUCUUGAACUCCUGGCCUCAAGCAAUCCUCCUGCCUCAGCCUCCCAAAGUGCUGGGAUUACAGGCAUGAGCCACCACAACCUGGCCUGCUUGGGUUUUUCUAUCUUGGCUCUGCCACCUAGCUGUGGGUCCUUGGACAAGUUACUUCAUCUCUCUGUGCCUCAGGUUUUUCAAAUGUAAAAUUGGGAUAAUUGGAUCUGUCUCAUAGGGUUGUGAAAAUUAAUGAGUUAAUGCUCUUAGAAGAGUACCUCAUAUGUAAUAAGCACGCAACUGUUAAUUAUUGUUAAUGUAGAAGUUAAUUCUGUGUAUAAAUCAGAUACACUGUGGUCAAAGAUUUGUGUGUAUUUGUAAGAAAAGAGGAGAAUGGAGAAUCUAUUUUUAAGUGGU